ACUCUCUGCUGUCGCCCGUCCCGCGCGCUCCUCCGACCCGCUCCGCUCCGCUCCGCUCGGCCCCGCGCCGCCCGUCAACAUGAUCCGCUGCGGCCUGGCCUGCGAGCGCUGCCGCUGGAUCCUGCCCCUGCUCCUACUCAGCGCCAUCGCCUUCGACAUCAUCGCGCUGGCCGGCCGCGGCUGGUUGCAGUCUAGCGACCACGGCCAGACGUCCUCGCUGUGGUGGAAAUGCUCCCAAGAGGGCGGCGGCAGCGGGUCCUACGAGGAGGGCUGUCAGAGCCUCAUGGAGUACGCGUGGGGUAGAGCAGCGGCUGCCAUGCUCUUCUGUGGCUUCAUCAUCCUGGUGAUCUGUUUCAUCCUCUCCUUCUUCGCCCUCUGUGGACCCCAGAUGCUUGUCUUCCUGAGAGUGAUUGGAGGUCUCCUUGCCUUGGCUGCUGUGUUCCAGAUCAUCUCCCUGGUAAUUUACCCCGUGAAGUACACCCAGACCUUCACCCUUCAUGCCAACCCUGCUGUCACUUACAUCUAUAACUGGGCCUACGGCUUUGGGUGGGCAGCCACGAUUAUCCUGAUUGGCUGUGCCUUCUUCUUCUGCUGCCUCCCCAACUACGAAGAUGACCUUCUGGGCAAUGCCAAGCCCAGGUACUUCUACACAUCUGCCUAACUUGGGAAUGAAUGUGGGAGAAAAUCGCUGCUGCUGAGAUGGACUCCAGAAGAAGAAACUGUUUCUCCAGGCGACUUUGAACCCAUUUUUUGGCAGUGUUCAUAUUAUUAAACUAGUCAAAAAUGCUAAAAUAAUUUGGGAGAAAAUAUUUUUUAAGUAGUGUUAUAGUUUCAUGUUUAUCUUUUAUUAUGUUUUGUGAAGUUGUGUCUUUUCACUAAUUACCUAUACUAUGCCAAUAUUUCCUUAUAUCUAUCCAUAACAUUUAUACUACAUUUGUAAGAGAAUAUGCACGUGAAACUUAACACUUUAUAAGGUAAAAAUGAGGUUUCCAAGAUUUAAUAAUCUGAUCAAGUUCUUGUUAUUUCCAAAUAGAAUGGACUCGGUCUGUUAAGGGCUAAGGAGAAGAGGAAGAUAAGGUUAAAAGUUGUUAAUGACCAAACAUUCUAAAAGAAAUGCAAAAAAAAAGUUUAUUUUCAAGCCUUCGAACUAUUUAAGGAAAGCAAAAUCAUUUCCUAAAUGCAUAUCAUUUGUGAGAAUUUCUCAUUAAUAUCCUGAAUCAUUCAUUUUAGCUAAGGCUUCAUGUUGACUCGAUAUGUCAUCUAGGAAAGUACUAUUUCAUGGUCCAAACCUGUUGCCAUAGUUGGUAAGGCUUUCCUUUAAGUGUGAAAUAUUUAGAUGAAAUUUUCUCUUUUAAAGUUCUUUAUAGGGUUAGGGUGUGGGAAAAUGCUAUAUUAAUAAAUCUGUAGUGUUUUGUGUUUAUAUGUUCAGAACCAGAGUAGACUGGAUUGAAAGAUGGACUGGGUCUAAUUUAUCAUGACUGAUAGAUCUGGUUAAGUUGUGUAGUAAAGCAUUAGGAGGGUCAUUCUUGUCACAAAAGUGCCACUAAAACAGCCUCAGGAGAAUAAAUGACUUGCUUUUCUAAAUCUCAGGUUUAUCUGGGCUCUAUCAUAUAGACAGGCUUCUGAUAGUUUGCAACUGUAAGCAGAAACCUACAUAUAGUUAAAAUCCUGGUCUUUCUUGGUAAACAGAUUUUAAAUGUCUGAUAUAAAACAUGCCACAGGAGAAUUCGGGGAUUUGAGUUUCUCUGAAUAGCAUAUAUAUGAUGCAUCGGAUAGGUCAUUAUGAUUUUUUACCAUUUCGACUUACAUAAUGAAAACCAAUUCAUUUUAAAUAUCAGAUUAUUAUUUUGUAAGUUGUGGAAAAAGCUAAUUGUAGUUUUCAUUAUGAAGUUUUCCCAAUAAACCAGGUAUUCUAAACUUGUUUCCAGUUUGUAGUUUUUCCAUUUUUCAAAUCUGGGGAAAGGAAUUAAAAAAAAAAUGGGUAAUAAGAACAUGGGAUAUAAUGAAAAGUGGUUUUUGUUUGUUUUUUUGUUUGAAGUUUUAAGGGCCUUGCUCAUUUUAGGUGUCCAAAACCAAUUUUUGAGUGGAGAUUAAUGAAUUCUAAUAGUCUAUUCCCUGAACUUUUCCUCAAUGAACAAUACCCUAGACACACAUUAAACAAUUUCUCUGCAGUGCUAUCAACCAGAGGAAAAUGGACUAAGAGAUUUCUGGCAGGUUCAGACACCCGGGGGACAUGUGUGCAGUGUAGCUGAAGCCUCCUCCUUGUGCUGGGGUCCCCUUCCAUUCAGGUGGUGGGGUAGCAGUCUCUCUAUUUUCCCCUUGCCCUCCUUCCCAUUUUAUCAUUUGUUAUUUUUUUUCCCACCAUAAGUCAUAUGUUACUUCCACUAUGGUGUAUGUCAUUGUGAGGAUGGGUGCAGAGAGGCUGGGUGGGAGAACGGAAAUAUAUCUCCCUAGGGCUACUGUUGGCCAGCUAGUCCUUGGCAGUGAAUUUUUCUAUGCUUUUCAAAAUGCGAGGUGAAUGUUUCUCAUAGAGAAAUGUAAUCUGGGUGAUUAUACCAAAAUUGAAAAGAAAAACCCACACAACUAUGCCGUGGCUGGUGGAGAAUUUGAAGUGGUCAUUAAAAAUGUUAAAAAUCCCAUCUUUUAAAGUGAUACCACAGCUCAUUCAAGAAGAUACUGGAUAUCUAGAGAUUAAGAAACGUGGUCUCCUGUUAAACAUGAAAAUGACUCCGUUUAUAAGCUUCUCUACCACAUGCACUUGUCUUUGCAUGAUUUCCCAUCCAGCCUUCUUCCCCUCCUCAAUCACACAAUACCUUAACGGCGCACAUUUAGGAAAAAUGCAACCUCCUGGGACCAACGAGCCUGAUAUAAUAGAACCAUGUCAACCUAAAGUAUUUAUGACAAAGAUAAACUCUUAUUUUGCAGAAAUGGUCUGCUUCCUUCAGCCUUGUUCUAGUAUAGAGAUCUGCCAUUCCUUGUUGAUCCAGAUUCACCAAGACAGAUACCUUUAUGUCAUAACAGAAGGGAAGUUCCAGAGGAUUCUGGAGAGUAAUGAAGAAUUGGGCUGAGAAACCACCUGAAGGCUAACAGUGCAUUGCAUGAGAUUUCCCACAGUAAAGCUGAGGUGCUUUUUGGUUCAGUAAUUAAAUAUUGAGUUCCCACCCUUUAAAUAAGCAGUUCUAGGUUCCUAAGCAAUUAUUUCACUCUGUAAGUAGCCAGACAUGCUAAGUGGCACUUACUGCUGAUUGUAACAAAGAAGUAAUAUAUCAAGGUCUUUCCAUGUUCACACAAGGUAGCUUGUGUGUAAUAACUUAGCUUCAAAACCAUAGACUGCAGAACUCACAAGUUCAACAGCCUUUCCUUUUUUAAGGAAAUGAAAACAAUGGAAAAUAUAGUCAUCAUAACUUAAUUCGGUUUAUUUUUUUUUUCUGUAAACUCCCCCUGAAAGACAUUCCUAUUAAUACAGUAAAUGUGAACACUGACUUGUUUUUAUAAGCACAUCUGAAAGGGCAUAUUUGAGUCUCAUCCCAACUUUGGUCCUUGCUAUCUGUGCAGGCUUGGGCAGGUCAUCUCCCUGCUGGUCUCAAUAUCCUCACCUGUAAAAUGAUUGUAAAUGAUCCCCCUACCUUCAAGAUUCUCUGAUUGAUAGAAUUUUUUCUUUAAUUAAAAAAUUUUAAAUAUUCCUUGAGUUGGAAGCACUGAUCAAUAAGUGGAUUGCUUAGGGAGGUUGGAACGAAUAGAUUCAGUCCCAACUUCCUCUUUUAAAUUCCCUCUUCCUCACUCUUCCUGCAACACUUAUUUUUACAGUUGAGUUUUAAAAAUAAGUAAUAUAUAAAAUAAUUUCUGUAGUGUGGUUUCAGAUUUAAAAAUUCCUGCAGACAGGCUGGGCUUGCAACCCCAUCAGUCGAUGGUCAGAGCCCUUUGCUUUUUGAGACCAUUUUUAGGUGAGCUUGGCUUGCCUGGAUACAGUGUGCAGUGCAUUCUUCCUGAAUUUUGCAAUUCUGGUAUCUGGGUGUAUUUUCUAGGUGUGUCAGGGUGAGUGUAAUCCACCUAGGGUGUGGAAAAAGCCAAGAAAGGGAAAUUAAAAGAGGUUCCUAUCCAGUCAUGUUAAUGAUCUUCCACUUGUACUAUCCUGUGCUUCGUUGUUAACCUCGAAAACAUACUUUGUUGGCUGCAAAAAUAAACAAAGGGAAACUCA